GCACUCCCAGCUAAAAGUAAAGAAGCAGAAAUAAAAAGGAUAAACAAGGAACUGGCAAAUAUCAGAUCAAAAUUUAAAGGUGACAAGGCUCUUGAUGGCUAUAGUAAAAAAAAGUACGUCUGCAAGUUGCUCUUCAUCUUUCUCCUUGGUCAUGACAUUGACUUUGGACACAUGGAGGCUGUGAACCUGCUGAGUUCAAACAGAUACACGGAAAAGCAGAUCGGCUACCUUUUCAUCUCUGUGUUGGUGAACUCAAACAGUGAGCUGAUCCGCCUGAUCAACAACGCCAUCAAGAAUGACCUGGCCAGCCGCAACCCCACCUUCAUGGGCCUGGCCCUGCACUGCAUCGCCAGCGUGGGCAGCCGGGAGAUGGCCGAGGCCUUCGCCGGGGAGAUCCCUAAGGUCCUCGUAGCCGGAGACACUAUGGACAGCGUGAAGCAGAGCGCGGCCCUGUGCUUGCUGCGCCUGUACAGGACGUCCCCCGAUCUUGUCCCCAUGGGCGACUGGACAUCCCGAGUGGUGCACCUGCUCAAUGACCAGCACUUGGGUGUGGUAACUGCAGCCACAAGUCUGAUCACCACUUUAGCACAGAAGAACCCAGAAGAGUUUAAAACCUCCGUGUCUCUGGCUGUCUCUAGGCUAAGCAGAAUCGUGACGUCUGCAUCCACAGAUCUCCAGGAUUACACUUACUAUUUUGUCCCGGCUCCCUGGCUGUCUGUCAAACUGCUGAGACUGCUGCAGUGCUACCCACCCCCAGAAGACCCUGCAGUGCGAGGCCGCCUGACUGAGUGCCUGGAGACCAUCCUGAACAAAGCCCAAGAACCGCCCAAGUCGAAGAAGGUCCAGCACUCCAACGCGAAGAAUGCCGUGCUCUUCGAGGCCAUCAGCUUAAUCAUUCACCAUGACAGUGAGCCGAACCUGCUCGUCCGUGCCUGCAACCAGUUGGGCCAGUUUCUGCAGCACCGCGAGACCAACCUGCGCUACCUGGCCCUGGAGAGCAUGUGCACGCUGGCCAGCUCUGAGUUCUCCCAUGAGGCUGUCAAGACGCACAUCGAGACGGUCAUCAACGCCCUGAAGACUGAGCGGGACGUGAGCGUGCGGCAGCGGGCCGUGGACCUCCUCUACGCCAUGUGCGACCGCAGCAACGCCCCACAGAUCGUGGCCGAGAUGCUGAGCUAUCUGGAGACAGCUGACUACUCCAUCCGAGAAGAGAUUGUGCUGAAGGUCGCCAUCCUGGCUGAGAAGUACGCGGUGGACUACACCUGGUAUGUGGAUACCAUCUUGAACUUGAUCCGAAUUGCUGGUGAUUACGUGAGUGAAGAGGUGUGGUACCGAGUCAUUCAGAUCGUCAUCAACCGGGACGACGUGCAGGGCUACGCGGCCAAGACUGUGUUCGAGGCUCUUCAGGCUCCCGCGUGCCACGAGAACCUGGUCAAAGUGGGCGGCUACAUCCUGGGGGAGUUUGGAAACUUGAUAGCUGGAGACCCGAGAUCCAGCCCGCUGAUCCAGUUCCACCUGCUGCACUCCAAGUUCCACCUGUGCAGCGUCCCCACCCGCGCGCUGCUCCUGUCCACCUACAUCAAGUUCGUGAACCUCUUCCCGGAGGUGAAGCCCACCAUCCAGGACGUGCUGCGCAGCGACAGCCAGCUCAGGAACGCAGACGUGGAGCUGCAGCAGCGUGCUGUGGAGUACCUGCGGCUCAGCACCGUGGCCAGCACCGACAUUCUGGCGACCGUGCUGGAGGAGAUGCCCCCAUUCCCGGAGCGGGAGUCCUCCAUCUUGGCAAAGCUCAAGAAGAAGAAGGGCCCCAGCACGGUGACAGACCUGGAGGACACCAAGCGGGACAGGAGUGUGGACGUGAACGGGGGUCCUGAGCCUGCCCCAGCCAGUACCAGCGCCGUGUCUACGCCUUCUCCGUCGGCAGACCUGCUGGGUCUCGGGGCUGCCCCCCCUGCCCCCGCGGGCCCCCCACCCUCCUCCGGCGGCAGCGGGCUGCUCGUGGACGUGUUCUCAGACUCGGCCUCUGUGGUCGCGCCUCUCGCUCCUGGCUCCGAAGACAACUUUGCCAGGUUUGUUUGUAAAAACAAUGGUGUGUUGUUUGAAAACCAGCUGCUUCAAAUUGGACUUAAGUCUGAAUUUCGGCAGAAUUUAGGUCGGAUGUUUAUCUUUUAUGGUAAUAAGACCUCCACGCAGUUCCUAAACUUUACCCCAACACUAAUCUGUUCAGACGACCUUCAGCCUAACCUGAACCUGCAGACCAAGCCCGUGGACCCGACCGUGGAGGGGGGCGCGCAGGUGCAGCAGGUGGUCAACAUAGAGUGCGUGUCCGACUUCACGGAGGCGCCAGUCCUCAACAUUCAGUUCAGGUAUGGGGGCACCUUCCAGAACGUGUCUGUGCAGCUGCCCAUCACUCUCAACAAAUUCUUCCAGCCGACAGAAAUGGCUUCUCAGGAUUUCUUUCAACGUUGGAAGCAGUUGAGCAAUCCACAGCAGGAAGUGCAGAACAUCUUCAAAGCAAAGCACCCAAUGGACACAGAAGUCACCAAAGCCAAGAUCAUUGGAUUUGGUUCUGCACUUCUUGAAGAAGUUGAUCCUAAUCCUGCGAAUUUCGUGGGAGCUGGAAUCAUCCACACGAAAACCACCCAGAUUGGAUGCCUGCUGCGCUUGGAGCCGAACCUGCAAGCCCAGAUGUACCGGCUCACGCUGCGCACAAGUAAGGAAGCCGUUUCUCAGAGAUUAUGUGAAUUGCUCUCAGCGCAGUUUUAGUCCUGAGGAUGGAAGACCAGGCUCGUGUGUCUUGUGUUGUCUUCGUCUGUGCCGUUUGUCUUCGUGGCUAUCCUGCAGAUGAGCACCGUGUCCAGUGCCACAGCACAAGGCGCCUCCCCGCCCCACCGCCCCACACCUCUCCCCUUUGGGCUGGACGGGAACACACGUGUGUGGCUCAGGAGGAAAAGCUCAGCCUGGACUGUGGCAGCCACGGCAGAAGGUGGAUCUUGGGAUCAAUUUUUAUAAAAAUCGAGACAGUUCUGUGGUUAAAUCUACAAAUUAAAGGGAAAUUAGAAGUUGGCGUGAACGUGGCGUUUGUGGGAGUGUCACUGAGAUGGCCCGUGCUGCCGCCCACCCCGCCUCGGAGCCUCUGGGAGCAGCAGUGCCACUGUGCAUGGCGUGGGCUGAGCCUUGGUGUGUGGCCGUCCUGGUGGCUGCACACCUGGCGUCGUCCUGGGCCCUUGGGAGGAGCACAGCUGACCCUGGUUUUGCUGCAGUCCCAGCUGGACUGUUUUCCCAGGCAGGAUUUUAAUCUAGAAUUUAGAAACAUUUGUAUUUGUAAUGACUUCUGGCAAAAGCACGUGUCCUGGCCGGAUGUAACUGUUCUCCUUUCCCAGCUCCUGUUUGUGAAGGGCGUCUGUUAUGCUCCUGCAGUCGCCGAGGCCUUGGAUGUGCAGCCAGGGGAGGAGCGUCCUGCCGGCCCCGCAGGGCCCCCAGGACUCCAGGGUAAAGUGUGGGCCGGUGGCGCAAGACUCAGAGGUGUGCUCGUCUCUUUCCUGUCAGAGUGGGCGUCCCCAGGCCACGGUGCAGGCCUGAGUCCUUCCACCGGCCCCGUCCAGUCGUCCCUGGAGGGGCUGUGGAGGAAGGACGCCUCUGUGUGGUCAGGAAGUGAAGGGGCCAUUGGCCGCAUGCCAUGUGCCACCUGCGGCUUGUGUCUCACCUGUCAUCUGGACUCAGCACCCAGGCUGCACGUCUGACACCUGAGAGGCGAGAGAGUGGGGCCGGCCUAGGAGCCAAGGCUGGGGCCUUGCGCUCUGUCCCCAGGAUGGUGGCCUUGUUUGUCCUAAACACACCCAGCACAGGUUCUGGCUUCCUGACAUGCUGUGGAGGCAGGGAGGGUGGGUGGCCACAUGUGCUUGAGGGUUUUCACCCUGGCCCUCAGUUGCCUGCUGUGCGGGUCCCUGGGGCAGCUGCAGGGGCUCACGGACCCAUCAGGGUCUCCACAGCUCCCCUGCAGUGUGUGCACCCCACAAUGUCUGCGGCUCUUCUUCCGGCGUGUCGGGCUUUGAUCACAGCAUAGCCACGUCAGUGGCGUGCGCCUCUCGCACAGGCCAUUCUGGGUCUGGUGGUGCCAGGUGCCGUGACACGCCGUGCUGGGCUUGUGCUGCAGCUGGGUGGUGUGGCCCUCAUUCUCAUGUUCCAGCUGCUGGGCAGUGCUCUGCCUGUGUGCUGCGCCUGCAGGCUGCGUGUGCUGCCGUGGAUCUCCUGCAUCCCUUGACCCCUCCCGCCAUCAGAGGAAAGGCUGCUCCCCGAGGCACCGCUUCCCUGUGCGGCGCUGCAGAGGGGCCCUCAGUGUGGCACUCCUCGUCAAAGAAAAAUAAAGGCUAGAACUGCA